AGAUGGGGGAAAGGGUGGAGGGGAGGAGAGAGACGGACUUGUUCCACAUCCCACACUGGGGGGAGGUGGCAAAGGGGAAACAGUCACCCCAGGGCCCUCGGCUCAUUGCCCCAAUCCCUCACACCACCCAGUGCAGCUUUCUGGGGAAAGGCAGAUUCUGGGGAUUGUCAGAGAAGAGUUUCCAGCCUCAAGUCCAGGCCUGUCCUCCCAAACUUUCCUUCUUCCUUGCCACUGCCUGCCAUCCCUUCUGAACCACAUUUGUCCUGGGACUGGAAGAGACAGGUAUCCCAUUUGGUCUUGGAACGCACAGAUCUCGUGGACAAGUGAUGGGAAAAAAUGAUCUCACAGCGUGAUGACGAAAGUAACUCAGGGGGCCAGAUGCAGUGGCUUAUGCCUGUAAUUCCAAUAACUCAGGAGACUGAGGCGCGAGGAUCGCUUGAGCCCAGGAGUUUGAGGCUGCAGUGAGCUAUGAUUGCAUCACUGCACUCCAGCCGGGGUGAAAGAGCAAGACCCUUUCUCUAAAAAGUAAAAAAGAAAGAAAGUAACUCAGGGCCAGACACAGUGGCUCAUGCUUGUAAUCCCAGUACUUUGGGAGGCUGAGGUAGGAGGAUCGCUUGAGCCCAGGAGUUCCAGACCAGUCUUGGCAACAUAGGGAGGCCCCCACCUCUACAAAAUAUUUAAAAAUUAGCCAUGUGUAGUGGUGCAUGCCUGCAUUGCCAGCUACUCAGGAGGCUGAGUUGGGGGAGGAUUGCUUAAGCCCAGGAGGUUAAGGCCGUAGUGUGCCUUGACUGUGCCACUGCACCCCAACCGGGGCGACAGAGCAAAACACGGUCUCAAAAAAAAAAAAAGGAAGAAAAGUAAAGAAACUCAGGGUACUGUGGGAGCACAGAGAAAAUUUUCUGGGUCAAAGAAGAUUCUAGCCAGGCCAUUCCCUGGAGGAAUCCACAGGCUGGUCUAGCUGUCAGACCAAGAUACAGACACAGCAUAAGUGAAGAGUGACUUAGAAUUUUCUUAGACAAGGACUCAGAUUCAGACUCUGAGGGAGGAGCCGCUGGUGGAGAAGCAGACAUGGACUUCCUGCGGAACUUAUUCUCCCAGACGCUCAGCCUGGGCAGCCAGAAGGAGCGUCUGCUGGACGAGCUGACCUUGGAAGGGGUGGCCCGGUACAUGCAGAGCGAACGCUGUCGCAGAGUCAUCUGUUUGGUGGGAGCUGGAAUCUCCACAUCCGCAGGCAUCCCCGACUUUCGCUCUCCAUCCACCGGCCUCUAUGACAACCUAGAGAAGUACCAUCUUCCCUACCCAGAGGCCAUCUUUGAGAUCAGCUAUUUCAAGAAACAUCCGGAACCCUUCUUCGCCCUCGCCAAGGAACUCUAUCCUGGGCAGUUCAAGCCAACCAUCUGUCACUACUUCAUGCGCCUGCUGAAGGACAAGGGGCUACUCCUGCGCUGCUACACGCAGAACAUAGAUACCCUGGAGCGAAUAGCCGGGCUGGAACAGGAGGACUUGGUGGAGGCGCACGGCACCUUCUACACAUCACACUGCGUCAGCGCCAGCUGCCGGCACGAAUACCCGCUAAGCUGGAUGAAAGAGAAGAUCUUCUCUGAGGUGACGCCCAAGUGUGAAGACUGUCAGAGCCUGGUGAAGCCUGAUAUCGUCUUUUUUGGUGAGAGCCUCCCAGCGCGUUUCUUCUCCUGUAUGCAGUCAGACUUCCUGAAGGUGGACCUCCUCCUGGUCAUGGGUACCUCCUUGCAGGUGCAGCCCUUUGCCUCCCUCAUCAGCAAGGCACCCCUCUCCACCCCUCGCCUGCUCAUCAACAAGGAGAAAGCUGGCCAGUCGGACCCUUUCCUGGGGAUGAUUAUGGGCCUCGGAGGAGGCAUGGACUUUGACUCCAAGAAGGCCUACAGGGACGUGGCCUGGCUGGGUGAAUGCGACCAGGGCUGCCUGGCCCUUGCUGAGCUCCUUGGAUGGAAGAAGGAGCUGGAGGACCUUGUCCGGAGGGAGCACGCCAGCAUAGAUGCCCAGUCGGGGGCGGGGGUCCCCAACCCCAGCACUUCAGCUUCCCCCAAGAAGUCCCCGCCACCUGCCAAGGACGAGGCCAGGACAACAGAGAGGGAGAAACCCCAGUGACAGCUGCAUCUCCCAGGCGGGAUGCCGAGCUCCUCAGGGACAGCUGAGCCCCAACCGGGCCUGGCCCCCUCUUAACCAGCAGUUCUUGUCUGGGGAGCUCAGAACAUCCCCCAAUCUCUUACAGCUCCCUCCCCAAAACUGGGGUCCCAGCAACCCUGGCCCCCAACCCCAGCAAAUCUCUAACACCUCCUAGAGGCCAAGGCUUAAACAGGCAUCUCUACCAGCCCCACUGUCUCUAACCACUCCUGGGCUAAGGAGUAACCUCCCUCAUCUCUAACUGCCCCCACGGGGCCAGGGCUACCCCAGAACUUUUAACUCUUCCAGGACAGGGAGCUUCGGGCCCCCACUCUGUCUCCUGCCCCCGGGGGCCUGUGGCUAAGUAAACCAUACCUAACCUACCCCAGUGUGGGUGUGGGCCUCUGAAUAUAACCCACACCCAGCGUAGGGGGAGUCUGAGCCGGGAGGGCUCCCGAGUCUCUGCCUUCAGCUCCCAAAGUGGGUGGUGGGCCCCCUUCACGUGGGACCCACUUCCCAUGCUGGAUGGGCAGAAGACAUUGCUUAUUGGAGACAAAUUAAAAACAAAAACAACUAACAA